CUUUCAUUUCCGCUUCCGGUGCGGGCCGCGCGCGAGCGCAGCGGUGGGAGGCGGCGACCAGCCGGUUGAGGCCCCAGGCUUGGCCUCACCACAAUGUGGCACGAGGCUCGGAAGCAUGAGCGGAAGCUUCGAGGCAUGAUGGUCGACUACAAGAAGAGGGCGGAGCGGAGACGGGAGUAUUAUGAAAAGAUCAAGAAGGACCCAGCCCAGUUCCUGCAGGUACAUGGCCGAGCUUGCAAGGUGCACCUGGAUUCUGCAGUCGCCCUGGCCGCUGAGAGCCCUGUUAAUAUGAUGCCCUGGCAGGGGGACACCAACAACAUGAUUGACCGAUUCGAUGUCCGUGCCCACCUGGACCACAUCCCCGACUACACCCCCCCUCUGCUCACCACCAUCUCCCCAGAACAGGAGUCGGACGAACGGAAGUGUAACUACGAGCGCUACAGAGGCCUGGUGCAGAACGACUUUGCCGGCAUCUCAGAGGAGCAGUGCCUGUACCAGAUCUACAUUGAUGAGUUGUACGGAGGCCUCCAGAGACCCAGCGAAGAUGAGAAGAAGAAGCUGGCAGAGAAGAAGGCUUCCAUCGGUUAUACCUACGAGGACAGCACGGUGGCCGAGGUAGAGAAGGCGGCAGAAAAGCCAGAGGAGGAGGAGUCAGCGGCCGAGGAGGAGAGCAACUCGGACGAAGAUGAGGUCAUCCCCGACAUCGACGUGGAGGUGGACGUGGAUGAAUUGAACCAGGAGCAGGUGGCAGAUCUCAACAAACAGGCCACGACUUAUGGCAUGGCCGACGGUGACUUCGUCAGGAUGCUCCGGAAAGACAAGGAGGAGGCAGAGGCCAUCAAGCAUGCCAAGGCUCUUGAGGAGGAGAAGGCCAUGUACUCGGGACGCCGCUCUCGACGCCAGCGGAGAGAGUUUCGGGAGAAGCGGCUGAGGGGUCGCAAGAUCAGCCCACCCAGCUAUGCCCGCCGAGACAGCCCCACCUAUGACCCCUAUAAGCGGUCACCCUCGGAGUCCAGCUCAGAGUCCCGCUCCCGCUCCCGCUCCCCGACCCCGGGCCGCGAGGAGAAGAUCACGUUCAUCACCAGUUUUGGGGGCAGCGAUGAGGAGGCAGCCGCAGCCGCUGCUGCCGCAGCAGCAUCAGGAGUCACCACAGGGAAGCCCCCCGCACCUCCCCAGCCUGGCGGCCCCGCCCCGGGACGUAAUGCCAGCGCCCGCCGCCGCUCCUCCUCCUCCUCCUCCUCCUCUUCUGCCUCGAGGACCUCCAGCUCCCGCUCCAGCUCUCGCUCCAGCUCCCGCUCUCGCCGUGGUGGGGGCUACUACCGUUCCGGCCGCCACGCCCGCUCCCGGUCCCGCUCCUGGUCCCGCUCCCGCUCCCGCUCCCGGCGCUAUUCCCGGUCCCGUAGCCGUGGCCGGCGGCACUCAGGUGGGGGCUCCCGAGACGGACACCGGUACUCCCGCUCGCCCGCCCGGCGUGGUGGUUACGGGCCCCGGCGCAGAAGCAGGAGCCGCUCCCACUCAGGGGACCGCUACAGGCGGGGCGGCCGGGGCCUCAGGCACCACAGCAGUAGCCGCAGCCGCAGCAGCUGGUCCCUCAGCCCGUCCCGCAGUCGCAGCCUGACUCGCAGCCGCAGCCAUAGCCCCAGCCCCAGCCAGAGCCGCAGCCGCAGCCGCAGCCGCAGCCAGAGCCCCUCGCCAUCACCCGCAAGAGAGAAGCUGACCAGGCCGGCCGCGUCCCCUGCUGUGGGCGAGAAGCUGAAAAAGACCGAACCUGCCGCUGGUAAAGAGACAGGAGCUGCCAAACCCAAGCUGACGCCUCAGGAGAAGCUGAAACUGAGGAUGCAGAAGGCGCUGAACAGGCAGUUCAAGGCGGAUAAGAAGGCGGCACAAGAAAAGAUGAUCCAGCAGGAGCAUGAGCGGCAGGAGCGGGAAGACGAGCUUCGAGCCAUGGCCCGCAAGAUCCGCAUGAAGGUGUUGGAAGCACCUGCCCUCCCUGAGUUCAGUGUGUCCAGUGUUCCCGGCCAGAUGCUCAUGCCAUGCCUUCGCAGGGAGCGGGAACGCCGAGAGAAGGAGAGAGAAGAGUGGGAACGCCAGUACAGCCGGCAGAGCCGCUCACCCUCCCCCCGAUACAGUCGAGAAUACAGCUCUUCUCGAAGGCGCUCAAGGUCCCGAUCCCGAAGCCCCCAUUACCGACAUUAGGCAGAAGAGUGGGGGGUGGGGAGGACAAGGGGGUGGGUAAGGGGCUCAAGCUGUGAUGCUGCUGGUUUUAUCUCUAGUGAAAUAAAGUCAAAAGUUAUUUAAUUCCCGUCA